GAUAAUGAGCUGCAUGGUGAAAUAGGGAGGCCGGCGCUCAGGGCUCCUCCGCCGCCGCCGCCGCCGCCGCCGCCGCCGCCACCGCGGGAGCCAGAGCUGCCGGGAGGAGCGGCAUCCGCGCCAGACUGGAGCGGGAGGGCGGCGGAGGGCAGUUGCUGGGAAUUUUUCAGCCGAGAGGGCGAGCGAUCCGGAGAGAGACCCCGAGAGCUUGGGAGCGGUAGGGCGUGCGAGCGCCGCAGCCAGCGGAGCAAACCUCGAAAUAGAUCUGGAAAGCCAGGCUCCCGGAGGAAAUGGGACUGUGAACGAACCGGAGAGCAAGAAGGGAAGGAAGCGCCGGGAUUGCUGAUGUCAGAGGAGCCCGGAAAGUCGCGCUGGAAAAAUCUGAAGACAGCCGGGGCUCUGCUUCUUCCUCAGGAGAGACACCGCCGGCCGCCCCCACACGCCCCCUCGGCGCCUCCGGGUGCCCCCUGAGAGCCGGCGACAGCGCCCAGCCGGGCUGCUGCGGGGCGACGGAGGACUGAGGGGCGCGCGGAGCGGAGACCGAGGAGCGACUUCAGGAAUACAGAUAAGUGUCUGGUGGCUUGACGUGGAUUUUAAUGAAUUUGGACUCCAUGUGGAUUUGGUCGUCUCCCUGAUUCCGAGCUGCGGGCAGGGAGAGGGGCCUCGCGCCGCCCUCAGCAGCCGGCGGCGGCCGAGGUAGACCGAGCGGGGACGGAAGGACAGACCGACGUCGCCGAGCUGGAAUCAUGUGAGGGCCAACCGGGGAAGGUGGAGCAGAUGAGCACACACAGGAGCCGUCUCCUCACCGCCGCCCCUCUCAGCAUGGAACAGAGGCGGCCCUGGCCCCGGGCCCUGGAGGUGGACAGCCGCUCUGUGGUCCUGCUCUCAGUGGUCUGGGUGCUGCUGGCCCCCCCAGCAGCCGGCAUGCCUCAGUUCAGCACCUUCCACUCUGAGAAUCGUGACUGGACCUUCAACCACUUGACCGUCCACCAAGGGACGGGGGCCGUCUAUGUGGGGGCCAUCAACCGGGUCUAUAAGCUGACAGGCAACCUGACCAUCCAGGUGGCUCAUAAGACAGGGCCAGAAGAGGACAACAAGUCUUGUUACCCGCCCCUCAUCGUGCAGCCCUGCAGCGAAGUGCUCACCCUCACCAACAAUGUCAACAAGCUGCUCAUCAUUGACUACUCUGAGAACCGCCUGCUGGCCUGUGGGAGCCUCUACCAGGGGGUCUGCAAGCUGCUGCGGCUGGAUGACCUCUUCAUCCUGGUGGAGCCAUCCCACAAGAAGGAGCACUACCUGUCCAGUGUCAACAAGACGGGCACCAUGUACGGGGUGAUUGUGCGCUCUGAGGGUGAGGAUGGCAAGCUCUUCAUCGGCACGGCUGUGGAUGGGAAGCAGGAUUACUUCCCGACCCUGUCCAGCCGGAAGCUGCCCCGAGACCCUGAGUCCUCAGCCAUGCUCGACUAUGAGCUACACAGCGAUUUUGUCUCCUCUCUCAUCAAGAUCCCUUCAGACACCCUGGCCCUGGUCUCCCACUUUGACAUCUUCUACAUCUACGGCUUUGCUAGUGGGGGCUUUGUCUACUUUCUCACUGUCCAGCCCGAGACCCCUGAGGGUGUGGCCAUCAACUCCGCUGGAGACCUCUUCUACACCUCACGCAUCGUGCGGCUCUGCAAGGAUGACCCCAAGUUCCACUCAUACGUGUCCCUGCCCUUCGGCUGCACCCGGGCCGGGGUGGAAUACCGCCUCCUGCAGGCUGCUUACCUGGCCAAGCCUGGGGACUCACUGGCCCAGGCCUUCAAUAUCACCAGCCAGGACGAUGUACUCUUUGCCAUCUUCUCCAAAGGGCAGAAGCAGUAUCACCACCCGCCCGAUGACUCUGCCCUGUGUGCCUUCCCUAUCCGGGCCAUCAACUUGCAGAUCAAGGAGCGCCUGCAGUCCUGCUACCAGGGCGAGGGCAACCUGGAGCUCAACUGGCUGCUGGGGAAGGACGUCCAGUGCACCAAGGCGCCUGUCCCCAUCGAUGAUAACUUCUGUGGACUGGACAUCAACCAGCCCCUGGGAGGCUCAACUCCAGUGGAGGGCCUGACCCUGUACACCACCAGCAGGGACCGCAUGACCUCUGUGGCCUCCUACGUUUACAACGGCUACAGCGUGGUUUUUGUGGGGACUAAGAGUGGCAAGCUGAAAAAGAUUCGGGCCGACGGUCCCCCCCAUGGUGGGGUCCAGUACGAGAUGGUCUCUGUGCUCAAGGACGGAAGCCCCAUCCUCCGGGACAUGGCCUUCUCCAUUGAUCAGCGCUACCUGUACGUCAUGUCUGAGAGACAGGUCACCAGGGUCCCCGUGGAGUCAUGUGAGCAGUAUACGACUUGUGGGGAGUGCCUGAGCUCUGGGGACCCUCACUGUGGCUGGUGUGCCCUGCACAACAUGUGCUCCCGCAGGGACAAAUGCCAACAGGCCUGGGAACCUAAUCGAUUUGCUGCCAGCAUCAGCCAGUGUGUGAGCCUUGCAGUGCAUCCCAGCAGCAUCUCAGUAUCUGAGCACAGCCGGUUGCUUAGCCUGGUAGUGAGUGAUGCUCCUGAUCUAUCUGCGGGUAUCGCCUGUGCCUUUGGGAACCUGACAGAGGUGGAGGGGCAGGUGUCCGGGAGCCAGGUCAUCUGCAUCUCACCUGGGCCCAAGGAUGUCCCUGUCAUCCCGCUGGAUCAAGACUGGUUUGGGCUGGAGCUACAGCUGAGGUCCAAGGAGACAGGGAAGAUAUUUGUCAGCACCGAGUUCAAGUUUUACAACUGCAGUGCCCACCAACUGUGCCUGUCCUGUGUCAACAGCGCCUUCCGCUGCCAUUGGUGCAAGUACCGCAACCUCUGCACUCAUGACCCCACCACCUGCUCCUUCCAGGAGGGCCGGAUCAAUAUUUCAGAGGACUGUCCCCAGCUGGUGCCCACAGAGGAGAUCUUGAUUCCAGUCGGGGAGGUAAAGCCAAUCACCCUUAAGGCGCGAAAUCUGCCCCAGCCGCAGUCCGGCCAGCGAGGCUAUGAGUGUGUCCUCAACAUACAAGGAGCCAUCCACCGGGUCCCCGCUCUGCGCUUCAACAGCUCCAGCGUUCAGUGUCAGAACAGCUCGUACCAGUAUGAUGGCAUGGACAUCAGCAAUCUGGCCGUGGAUUUCGCUGUGGUGUGGAACGGCAAUUUCAUCAUUGACAACCCUCAGGACCUGAAAGUCCAUCUCUACAAGUGUGCAGCCCAGCGGGAGAGCUGCGGCCUCUGCCUCAAGGCCGACCGGAAGUUUGAGUGUGGCUGGUGCAGCGGCGAGCGCAGGUGCACCCUCCACCAGCACUGUACCAGCCCUUCCAGCCCCUGGCUCGACUGGUCCAGCCACAAUGUCAAGUGCUCCAACCCUCAAAUCACCGAGAUUUUGACGGUGUCUGGACCGCCGGAAGGAGGGACGCGAGUGACCAUCCAUGGCGUGAACCUGGGUCUGGACUUCUCCGAGAUCGCCCACCAUGUGCAGGUGGCUGGGGUGCCCUGCACGCCCCUCCCAGGGGAAUACAUCAUCGCUGAGCAGAUUGUCUGUGAGAUGGGCCAUGCCCUCGUGGGAACCACCUCCGGGCCAGUACGCCUGUGUAUUGGCGAGUGUAAGCCAGAGUUCAUGACGAAGUCCCAUCAGCAGUACACCUUCGUGAACCCUUCUGUGCUGUCACUCAACCCAAUCCGAGGUCCCGAGUCAGGAGGCACUAUGGUGACCAUUACCGGCCAUUACCUUGGGGCUGGGAGCAGCGUGGCAGUCUACCUGGGCAACCAGACCUGCGAGUUCUACGGGAGGUCAAUGAGUGAGAUCGUGUGUGUCUCACCCCCAUCAUCCAAUGGCCUUGGCCCGGUCCCUGUUUCUGUGAGUGUCGACCGAGCCCAUGUGGAUAGCAACCUGCAGUUUGAGUACAUAGAUGACCCUCGGGUCCAGCGCAUCGAGCCAGAGUGGAGCAUUGCCAGUGGCCACACACCCCUGACCAUCACAGGCUUCAACCUGGAUGUCAUUCAGGAGCCAAGGAUCCGAGUCAAAUUCAAUGGCAAAGAAUCUGUCAAUGUGUGUAAAGUUGUGAACACAACCACCCUCACCUGCCUGGCACCCUCUCUGACCACGGACUACCGCCCUGGCCUGGACACUGUGGAACGCCCAGAUGAGUUUGGAUUUGUCUUUAACAAUGUCCAAUCCUUGCUAAUUUACAACGACACCAAGUUUAUCUACUACCCCAACCCGACCUUUGAACUGCUUAGCCCUACUGGAGUCUUGGAUCAAAAGCCAGGAUCGCCCAUCAUUCUGAAGGGCAAAAACCUCUGCCCUCCUGCCUCUGGAGGGGCCAAACUCAACUACACUGUGCUCAUCGGAGAGACCCCUUGUGCUGUCACCGUAUCUGAGACCCAGCUUCUCUGCGAGCCUCCCAACCUCACCGGGCAGCACAAGGUCAUGGUUCACGUGGGCGGGAUGGUGUUCUCGCCUGGCUCGGUGAGUGUCAUCUCAGACAGCUUGCUGACCCUGCCAGCCAUCGUCAGCAUCGCGGCCGGCGGCAGCCUCCUCCUCAUCAUCGUCAUCAUCGUCCUCAUUGCCUACAAGCGCAAGUCUCGAGAAAAUGACCUCACUCUCAAGCGGCUGCAAAUGCAGAUGGACAAUCUGGAGUCCCGUGUGGCCUUGGAGUGCAAGGAAGCUUUUGCUGAGCUCCAGACGGAUAUCAAUGAGUUGACCAGUGACCUGGACCGCUCAGGAAUCCCUUACCUGGACUAUCGUACCUACGCUAUGCGAGUCCUGUUCCCGGGCAUCGAGGACCACCCCGUCCUGCGGGAGCUGGAGGUACAAGGAAACGGGCAGCAGCACGUGGAGAAGGCCCUGAAGCUCUUUGCCCAGCUCAUCAACAACAAGGUGUUCCUGCUGACCUUCAUCCGCACCCUGGAGCUGCAGCGCAGUUUCUCCAUGCGCGACCGGGGCAACGUGGCUUCGCUCAUCAUGACCGGCCUGCAGGGCCGCCUGGAAUAUGCCACUGAUGUCCUCAAGCAGCUGCUCUCUGACCUCAUCGAUAAGAACCUGGAGAACAAGAACCACCCCAAGCUGCUACUCCGGAGGACAGAGUCUGUGGCUGAAAAGAUGCUGACCAAUUGGUUCGCCUUCCUCCUGCACAAGUUCCUAAAGGAGUGCGCAGGGGAGCCACUCUUCAUGCUAUACUGUGCCAUCAAGCAGCAGAUGGAGAAGGGCCCCAUUGAUGCCAUCACGGGCGAGGCCCGCUACUCCCUGAGCGAGGACAAGCUCAUCCGGCAGCAGAUCGAGUACAAGACCCUGAUCCUGAACUGCGUCAACCCUGACAACGAGAACAGUCCAGAGAUCCCAGUGAAGGUGUUAAACUGUGACACCAUCACACAGGUCAAGGAGAAGAUUCUUGAUGCCGUGUAUAAGAAUGUGCCCUAUUCCCAGCGGCCGAGGGCAGUGGACAUGGACUUGGAGUGGCGCCAAGGCCGGAUCGCCCGGGUCGUGCUGCAAGAUGAGGACAUCACCACCAAGAUUGAGGGUGACUGGAAGCGGCUCAACACACUGAUGCAUUAUCAGGUGUCAGACAGGUCGGUGGUGGCUCUGGUCCCCAAACAGACCUCCUCCUACAACAUCCCUGCCUCUGCCAGCAUCUCCCGGACGUCCAUCAGCAGAUACGACUCCUCCUUCAGGUAUACGGGCAGCCCCGACAGCCUGCGGUCCCGGGCCCCGAUGAUCACCCCAGACCUGGAAAGUGGGGUCAAGGUGUGGCAUCUGGUGAAGAACCAUGACCACGGUGACCAGAAGGAGGGUGACCGGGGCAGCAAGAUGGUGUCCGAGAUCUACCUGACCCGGCUACUGGCCACCAAGACUCUCCUGGUCCUGCUGUGCUCCUGCCAGGAGGCACCCAGUCCUCCAGCUUGUUCCUCGGACACUGUUUCCGGACUGGCUUGCAGCCUGUGCCCCCUCAUUCACCCAUGGGAAGCCCGGACCCGGGGCACUUCCUGUCUUCCUGUCAAAGACCCUGAGCCUACACCCUGUGUGGAAUGUGGAAUGUGGCUGCAGGGCACCCUGCAGAAGUUUGUGGACGACUUGUUUGAGACCUUGUUCAGCACUGUGCACCGGGGCAGCGCUCUCCCCCUGGCCAUCAAGUACAUGUUUGAUUUCCUAGAUGAGCAGGCAGACAGGCACAGCAUCCAUGACACAGAUGUGCGGCACACCUGGAAAAGCAACUGCCUCCCUCUGCGCUUCUGGGUGAACGUGAUUAAGAACCCCCAGUUCGUGUUUGACAUCCACAAGGGCAGCAUCACGGACGCCUGCCUCUCUGUGGUGGCCCAGACCUUCAUGGACUCUUGUUCAACGUCAGAGCACCGGCUGGGCAAGGACUCCCCCUCCAACAAGCUGCUCUAUGCCAAGGACAUCCCCAGCUACAAGAGCUGGGUGGAGAGAUACUACGCAGACAUCGCCAAGCUCCCAGCCAUCAGUGACCAGGACAUGAAUGCCUACCUCGCCGAGCAGUCCCGCCUGCACGCCGUGGAGUUCAACAUGCUGAGUGCCCUCAAUGAGAUCUACUCCUAUGUCAGCAAGUAUAGUGAGGAGCUCAUCGGGGCCCUAGAGCAGGAUGAGCAGGCACGGCGGCAGCGGCUGGCUUAUAAGGUGGAGCAGCUCAUUAAUGCCAUGUCCAUUGAGAGCUGAGAGGAGGAGCCUCGCAUUCCUGGGAAGAGGGACCUGUCCAAGCUGUCACACUGGGAGUCUCAGAUGGAAGGACAAGUGAUGGGGAUCAGGCCCCAGAGCUUGCUGUCCCCUGAGACCCCAUCCUGGGGAGAGGGGAGGACUCCUCUCCCUACGCCAGCCAAGUUUCGUCAUAGCCAGUUCCAGCUGGGAGAGACAGUGGGCGUCGUCCAUCCUCAGUGAGAACACCAGAGAACCCGGGGCCGGGAGAAGGUGGUUCUUCAAGCCGAGAGGCACGAGCUGGGGACAGUUCUGCCUCUGUGACUGCUGCUUUGCAUGAAAACUCAUUUGAUGUAUAUUGGGGAAAUAAUGAGAACUUUAUUUAAUUUUUUUAAGAAAAAGGGAAAAAAACAGAAAUAAAACAAAAAGCCGCCCUGUUAAUCCCGUCCAACUUUUGUUUAAUUCUGAUUUCUGUCUCCCUUCCAUCUUUUCUCCCAUUCCUCCUUCUUUAUAUAAUGCCUAUUUCCAAAUGCCAGAGAAAGCAGAGAUGCUGAGAGACAUUGGAGAGAAAAUGACUGUCUCCUUUUCCUUGAAAUUAAAAAAAAAAAAAAAAAGAGAAAGAGGAGAAGAAGAAUGAUGAGCACAAGUAUGCACCAAACACUUCGCAAAAACAGAGGCCAGUAAAACCUGGAAUUAUCCCGGCAGCCAGAGGAGUAUGGAACUUCCAGAACUUUGCACAAAUUGCAAAGCCAUCAAGAGCUCACCCUGGCUGACUGGAAACUGAGCUUUAUCUACCACACACCUGUAUAUUCUCAUCUUUUGAGAGGAGAUGUGUACCUAGAUAGUACCAAUGCUUUUUGCUACUGUUUUUUGUUUUGUUUUAUUUAAUCCUAAACCUCAACAAAUGAGGAGCUGGUCUUUGAUAUGUUUCCUUUCAAUUUCCCUAAAGUUACUAUGAGAAGUGGGGUGAGGUGGGCCUCUCCCAGACCAGACACCUGGCAGCCCUGCCUCAUAUCAAUCCCUGUCAUAAACCAGGCACCCUGGGGAAACGGCCUGGAGGUGUGUGGGCCAGGCCUCCACGAGGUUCCAUUUGAAAGUUGAUUUGGAGACAUAGGUGUUUGACUUUGGAGUUCACUCCAAUCAUCCAGUGGUCCCUGGCAAUUAAAAAGAAAACAAAAAUCAAACACUGUUUACAGCAAGCAAUACUUGAAGAGCAUAGGUUACAGAAGCUGCAGUAUUUAUUAUUAUGCUUUCUUUCUUUCAUUCUCUCGUGCCUGGAGAGGGGAGACCACCCUUCGCUCAUAUACGGAAGCUCCUGACCAUCUGGGCCUACAGCACUUCCUCAGUAGAAAUGACUGUGGCAUGCCCACGUUACUACCUUCUGCCUCUCUUUCUGCCUCUCACGGACUUGUGAGUGUGAAGGACAAGUGGAUGACUUCUCACUGGACUUUCCUUCUCUGUCUCUUCUGAUGAUGCCUAAAACUAUGGAUAACCAAUUCUCCUGAGUGUAGAUUCCAAACAAAGAGACCAAAGCUCCAUGCCCAGGUCCAAAGGCCCCAUAGAAGCCAGUGGGAGUCAUCGAGAGGAAAGGCGCUCUGUGAGUGUCAGGACCUUGGUGGCCAGGAUAGCCAUCAGAGUGUCCAGGCCUCCCACAUUACCUUGGAUCCGAGCAGCCAGCUCCAACUGUUCUGCAAGCAGCACUGGAGUCAGGGGGUAGGAGGACAAGUGGAAGCAAAGGUGUGGGACUGGGGAAGACAAAGAGGAACAAGCUGCCCUUCCUCACUUUUCAAAGGGUCAGGAAUCCUAGGCUAUGAUGCUGGGAAGCUAGACCAGCUCCUCCAAGAGAGACUAGACCAGGGUCAUUUUCUCUGUUAUUAACUCUGGGCUCCAGCUUCUCCGUGCCCUGCUUUACCUCCAAGUGGUUCCAAUUUCCAAAGGCCCUGCUGACCACAUGUGAUUCCCAGGAGAGGGCUGGGGGAGGGGAGCGCAGAGGUCUGGCUUCCAUCCUUGGCGUGUAGCUUUGGAUCGCUGUCUAACCACACAGCAGACGUUGCCCGGUCUCCCCAGCUCUAGUUUCUUGCCUGAAUGCGGCUGACAAAUGGGAAGAGAAAAGCAUUCAGCAAAAUACUCAGGAAACUUGCUGUUUUCAUUAUAAUUCACAACCAGCCAUGCCAAGGCCACUUUCUUUUGAAAAUCCACUUCUUUAAAGUUUCUCAGGCCCUAUUAGUAGCCUGAAGGAAAUACUAAUGACUGGCCUUCCGCACUAAGCCAAAGUGUUUGCUCUUCAUAGCACUCAAAGCUUAUCAGCGCAGAGCCCAUAAUUUAUGGAGAUAAAAGGAAAGGAGAUAUAGGUAAGAAGAGUGUGACCAGGAGACCUUAUGCUACCUGUAAAAAAGUUCAGCCCACCCCAUCUAACUUCUGAGCUCUGUUUGGGUGAAGAUUUUCUGGCCGCAUGGCUGCUCAGACUGGCAUCCAGGCUUUGCUCCACCAAGAAGUUAAAGGCAGUCGGACAUCUCAGUAGCAUCUCUACCAGCCCUUAACUCAAUGCAUCUACCUGGCAUCUCCCAGCAGUUACUUUUGGAGACGAUUCACUGCCCCUGGGGCGUUUCCUUGAAGGUUUGUGGAGAGCGUGGAGAAUGAUGGGGCAAUGGCCAAUUGGAGGGUGGAGAGUGAAGAGCCGGAGCUGGCUGUGAGUGGUUUGGCCACAUUUCUCAGGAUUCCAUGAGAGACUUGGGGAACUUGGGCUGACAAAGGAAGUAGCCUGGGGCAUCCUUAAGGAAGGAAUUAAGAAAAGGGAAAAAGCUGGACUCAAGCCACGCCAUGAGGGUGAAAGGUUAUAAGGCCCUGCCCCCUUUCCAGCUGCCCACCUGUUCCUCCUCCACACCUCUUCGCUUUGGGCCACCAAGAACCAAUGAAGUCCACACCCUUUGGAUGAGAAAAAGAGGGAGUUGGUUGGCCUCUCUUCUCCCUGUUAUCCAAUUUGAGGAUAUUUUGACCUUGGGUAAGGAUGAAGUGUUAAAGCCACAGCUCCUCUCCACAAGAAGCCAUUCAUCUUGGGGGAGGCAGAGAGGGAAGUCUCUCUCCAAAGUCUAUCCAGCUUCGCUUCGUUUCAUUGAUCUGCACAAGAGACAAUGCUCUGGAAAAGGAAGAGGACCCCAGAAGGGUGCUUGGCAAGACAGAGGAUGCUAAUGGGCAAUGGAGAGCACUCCCUCCAGCUGGCCCCUGCUGCUGCCUCCCGUCCUCUGCAUGGGGUCAGGUGCUUCUGUGCUUGCUGUCCUACCUCUCUCCACAGCAGGGCUCUCAAAACCAUUUUGAUCCCCCAUUGGCAGAGGGUUCCCCUCUUUACAGAGUUCAGUCAUUAAAAGCAUGGAUCAGCUGUUAAUCUCAUUGGAGGAGGGAACUGUUUCCUGCAUUCAUUCAUCUGGGAACCUUCUUGAGUAGCCACUGUCUGCCAGCCACUGCUCUAGAGAUGGGAAAACAGCACGGAACAAAACCAAGGUCUUUCUUCCAGCGAAUUUAUAUCCUUCAGGAAGCUGGUUCCUGCCACCAACUUAGCAGGCAACAGUUCUCCUCCCCUAGUGGCACAGGGUACCAGUUUUGUAGGAAAAGUGGUCCAGCAAAGGAAGAAAGCAGACCAACCCAGCUGCCUUACCUUAUUCUGGGGCCAUUCCCCCAGCGAUGAGAGCUGCUCUUGUUUCUACUGCCACCAUCUCUUCUGGCUGCACUUCACCUGCUGCUUGAGCUUCUGACCUUCCUUCAGUUCCACCAAAUGAGGACAGGAAAUAGCAGUCAAGACCCCUGGCCCUGCUGAGCGUGAAACAGAAGCAAUGGAUGAGUGCUGGACGAAGAAUGGCCUGGGCAGAACAAAUAGGGAGCAUUUGAAAGCUUCUGGCUGAUAAAUCUCCAGGUGCAUCCCGGUUGCCACGCCUGCCCCCAUUAACCUGCUCCUGGUAAAUACUGAUCCAGCAGCUGCUCCAGGAGAGGCCGUCUUUUUUUCCCAGCCACGCUGUGUCUUGCAUGAGACUCCUGGGGCCUGGGCACAGAGAGAAAAGAAUUGAGACUCAGGAGGCUCAGUGGGUGAGAAAAUGCAAAGUGGCUUCACAGACACAGGGCUGUGGGAGCAGAUCGACGGGGAACUUGGGAGAUGAACUUCAGGGCCUUCCGACGCCUUGUCUCAGGAACAUGCUUUGAGAAAAAUGGUAGCAUCCUUUCCAUAACUCAGUCUCUCUUCCCUAGUUUCCCUGAAGUGUGACGUUUUAGUAUCUGGAGCUCAGUGAUCCCCAUGAAUGAGGGAUAAAGUUUCACUCUUGGUAUUUUCUAACUAGUGCUAGGGAAAGUCCUGAGACACGAUCACAGCCACUGCUUGGCAUACAGGGCCUCCACCCAAUAAGCAAACUGGAGAUUCCUCAGCCUCUCGUGGACACCCACAUCUCAUUCUUCUCACAGCAGAGAAGCUCUCCCUUCAGCCUGAGCUGUCUUCUUUCUGCUGCAGUGCAGCCUGCUCCCUCCUACCCUGGCCUCAAGGAAGGUAGGAAACAUCUUCUGCAUUUCAAAGUCCUCACUUUGACUUAUUUGGCCUUCAUCUUGGCAUGGAAGGUGGCAGGCAGAAUGGAAAUACUCCCCCCAAACAGAACAGAUAUUCUUGCGUGUGUAAGGGCAGAAGGGACAAGCUCUCUAUCCCAUGAGACUAGGGGCCGGAGCCCACCUGCCUUUCCCCACAACUUUUCCUGCUCAAACCCACUCCUCUUGACACACUGGAAUCUGUAUUAUAUAUAUUUUUAAGAAAAUACAAUGAUGGUUGUCUGGUUUUGUUGUUUUUACAGGUGUUGUGGAAUAAAAACUGUAAGAAAAUUAAGUAUUUAAAAUGUUCCAAUAAAGUGGGGUUUUUUGUUAUUCUAAUAUAUUAUUGUGUACCUAUUGUAAAUAUGAAACACUCCUAUUUUGCAAGCUGAGGACACAAUUUGUACUGUUGUUAUAUAUAAAUAAAGUUUACUGAAUUAAAAAAACCUUAAAUCUUUAAAUAAA